AGAAACCUCCGGGGCGCUGCAGGCGGGACAAGCAGGUUCCACAGGCCGAGCCCACGAGCCCCUCGAGGGGUGAGCGGCCCGGGCCUCCUGGCGUUCUGGCCGGCUAGCCAAGCGCUGGACUACAUUUCCCAGAGGCACGGCGUCCGGAGCGCUGGACUACAUUUCCCAGAGGCACCGCUCCCGGAGCGUAGCUUCAUUUCCGUUAGUUUGCGAGAUUUGGAGGCCUCGCGUGGGGAGAGGGCCGCGUCUGUGGAGGAGCUUGGCUCCGCACCUGCUGGGCUGGCGAACCCGAAAUUGGGCUUGGAACCCGGGAGCCAGAUCUUGGACCCUGAACUGCACCUCUGUCAAGAGCCCAGAGGAGAAAGAAUGGCUGUUUCAGUAGCAAUGUCCAAGCUCUGCAUUCUCCAGACUCUGUGCUUUCCUAAGAUAGGAACCCAGAAGAGGACUGAUCAUUUCUUGCAGCUCUAAAAACCAUGGCUCGGAAAUUAGUGAUGUUCAGGGAUGUUGCCAUUGACUUCUCUCAGGAAGAGUGGGAAUGCCUGGACUCUGCUCAGAGAGAUUUGUAUAGAGAUGUGAUGUUGGAGAACUAUAGCAACUUGGUAUCACUAGCACUCUGAAGAUAUUAUUCCACUGUCCUCUGGCUUCUAUUGUUGCUCUUGAGAAGUCUGCCAUCUGUUUCAUUGUUAUUCCUUUUACUUGCCUUCAAGGUGUGCAAGUAAGGACUUAUCUCCAGAAAAGAACACUUAUGAAACAGAAUUAUCCCAAUGGGAAAUGAGUGACAGACUUGAAAACUGUGAUCUUGAAGAGUCCAAUUCCAGGGAUUAUUUGGAAGCCAAAGGCAAGAUGGAGAAGCAACAAGAAAAUCAGAAGGAAUAUUUCAGGCAAGGGAUGAUCAUAUAUGACAAAAUGUCCAUUUUCAACCAGCAUACUUACUUAUCUCAACAUUCAAGAUGUCAUUCUACUGAGAAACCCUAUAAAUGUAAGGAAUGUGGGAAAGCCUUCAGACGAGCCUCACACCUAACACAACAUCAAAGUAUUCAUACUGGUGAAAAACCCUAUGAAUGUAAGCAAUGCGGGAAGGCCUUUAGUCGUGAUUCACAACUCAGUCUUCAUCAGAGACUUCAUACUGGUGAGAAACCCUAUGCAUGUAAGGAAUGUGGGAAGGCCUUUACUCAAAGCUCACAACUUAUUUUACAUCAUAGAAUUCAUACUGGUGAAAAACCAUAUAAAUGUGAAGAAUGUGGGAAAGCCUUUAUUCGUAGCUCACAACUUACCCGACAUCAAAAAGUUCAUACUGGUGAGAAACCUUAUGAAUGUAAAGAAUGUGGGAAGGCCUUUACUCAGAAUUCACAACUUACACUACACCAGAGACUUCAUACUGGUGAAAAGCUCUAUGAAUGUAAAGAAUGUAGGAAGGUCUUUACUCAGCUCUCACAACUUAUUCUGCAUAAGAGAAUUCAUACCGGUGAGAAACCCUAUGAAUGUAAGGAAUGUGGAAAAGCUUUUAUUUGUGGCUCACAGCUUUCUCAACAUCAGAAAAUUCAUAAUGGGGAAAAACCAUAUGAAUGUAAGGAAUGUGGAAGGGCCUUUAUUCGGGGCUCACUACUGAUGCAACAUCAGAGGAUUCAUACUGGUGAAAAACCCUAUAAAUGUGAAGAAUGUGGGAAGGCCUUUAUCCGUGGCUCACAACUUACUCAACACCAGAGAAUUCACACCAAUGAAAAGCCCUAUGAAUGUAAGGAAUGUGGAAAGAUGUUUAGUCAUGGCUCACAACUUACUCAACAUCAGAGAAUACACACUGGUGAGAAACCCUAUCAAUGUAAGGAAUGUGGAAAAGCGUUUAAUCGUGGCUCACUCCUUACACGACACCAGAGGAUUCAUACUGGUGAGAAACCCUAUGAAUGUAAAGAAUGUGGAAAAACCUUUAGUCGUGGCUCAGAACUUACUCAACAUGAGCGAAUUCACACAGGUGAGAAACCCUAUGAAUGUAAGGAAUGUGGGAAAUCUUUUAUUCGUGGUUCCCAGCUUACUCAACAUCAGAGAAUCCAUACUGGUGAGAAACCUUAUGAAUGUAAAGAAUGUAGAAUGGCCUUUACUCAGAGUUCACAUCUUUCCCAACAUCAAAGACUUCACACUGGUGAGAAACCCUAUGUGUGUAAUGAAUGUGGAAAGGCCUUUGCGCGUGGCUUACUACUUAUACAACAUCAGAGAAUUCAUACUGGUGAGAAACCAUAUCAAUGUAAGGAAUGUGGGAAAGCCUUUAUUCGUGGUUCACAGUUGACUCAACAUCAGCGAAUUCACACUGGAGAAAAACCCUAUGAAUGCAAGGAGUGUGGCAAGGCCUUUAGUCAUGGCUCUCAGCUUACUCUACAUCAGAGAAUCCAUACUGGUGAGAAGCCCUAUGAAUGCAGAGAAUGUAGAAAGGCCUUUACUCAGAGUUCACAUCUUUCUCGGCAUCAGAGAAUUCAUACUGGUGAGAAACCAUAUCAAUGUAAGGAAUGUGGGAAGGCCUUUACUCGUGGUUCACAGCUAACUCAACAUCAGAGAAUUCAUAUCAGUGAGAAAUCUUUUGAAUAUAAGGAAUGUGGGAUUGACUUUAGUCAUGGCUCACAAGUUUACAUGUGAAUUGUCUGAUUAUUUGAGAUCACUAUGAAGAGGUUCUCUGGUUGUUAGCAGCAAAGAAUUCUCACAAAUGUGAAUAUGGGCGCACAUUUGCCUCAUAAAGCACAGCAUCAGAUAAUUUAUGUGAGAGAAAAUGGUAGUGUCAUUCAUAUAGAAAAACAUCAUUACUGGAAACCUAUUAAACAUUAGCAAAUUGGAGAAUAGUUUUAAUAUAGUAAAUGUAGGAAGCCCUUUAGCCAUAUUGAAAACAAAUAUCUUUUUCAACGUUAUCUUAGCUCUACUAGUUGAUCUUUUUGUUAUAUGUAUCAUGAUACUUAACCUCUACCUUGGUUUAAUCAUUUUAAGAUAGACCUAAGUAUAUUACCUUUAUUGUAAGAUUCUUGGAAGUAUUAUGUAAGUUAUUACAUGUAAAAGCUCUUAGAAUGGUGCCUUGAACGUAGCAUACCACAAAUAUUAGCUACCAUUUUCACUAGUGUUAUUUUAGAGAAUUUGCAUGAGAGGAGAGUACUUAUGAGUAUAAUGAAUAUUGAGAAAUCUUUUAUCAACACAUCCAAGAUGACUUGGUUGGGGGGCACUGUAUGCCAUAAUGAAUGUGAGAAAGCUGUCAUUUAAAUCUCAUCCAUUAUUGCUAUAAGAGGAAAUUCAUACUGUUAAAAAAAAAAAAACCCAGUGGAUAUAAUCAGUGUAUUAUUAAAAAAAAAAAAACCCAGUGGAUGUAAUCAGUGUAUUAUUGAGCACAGCUGUUAGAGAAGUGGGACAAGGUGUGAAGUGAUUUUUAACGAAGUCUAAGAUCCAAAGUCUAAUAAAUCUAGGAAUUUUUUAAAAACUUGAAUGUAUUGCUUUUGAAGUAAACAAAAUAACUGAUAUUACAGACUAUUUUGCAAUGAAAAAUGAUGAGAGUUUGUGAUACAGACUGCUUUUUUCCUACCCUAUAUCUAUUUUCUCUUUUUUAGUAACAAAUUUCUGGGCUGAAAAUCUCAGCCUUCCUUGCAGGUCAACAAGAUAGAAGUGAUAUUUAUAUGAGUAGGAGAUUUACGAAAUCCAUUUUUCCUGUCUUUUUUUCCGUGCCUACAAUGUGGACAUCUAAGCUGGAGCUCCGUUACUCUCAUGGGGACUUUGAGAAUGGUAUCUGGGUGUUAUGGAUCAUGGAGCAGAAAUACAGAAGGAGUCUGCAACCCUGAUGACUUUGUGGAACAGCCAUACUAGCUCUGGUCUGCUUGCCUCCUGUUUCUCUUUAAAUAAAAUUAAACAUCUUAUUUGUUGAUGCUAUUGUAGUUCUGUUAUUGACAAUAAAAAUUCUUAAGGAUAUAAA